CCCCUAGCGAAGGCGGGGACUCGGGCGCUGUUGGCAGCUGGCGACGCGGGGCGAAGCCGCGGCUGGCGGCGCCUGGCCAGUCCCGCAUCCGCCGCGGUGGGUGUGCCCGCAGGGGUGCGCCGGGGCCAGGGCCGAGACCGUCGGCCAGAGGGCGCCUGGAGGGUGUGCGCGCCGCGGACGACCAGGGUGCGCCAGCCCCGGGGUGCGCGCCUGGGACGCGGACAGUGCACCCGGAGGUUGCGUGCGCUCCGAAGCCGGGGUGUGCGCCUAGCUGCCCCGGCCCCGUGCACCGCGGGCCGCCUCGCGCAGGACUUCCGCAGCUCGCCAAGAACUGCAGCAGCUUUGGGCUGUAGGAAGACCCUCCACUGUGCUUGCCCGGGACACUCUGAAACCUUGCUCCUCUGGCAGCUGCCUGCUCCCUGGCUCCUGCACCCCGCCUCUCGGAGUCUCUGGUCUGCGCUGCAGUUAGAAACCCUGCCUGGAAGUGGAUCCACUGAACAGUAAUUUGGUCGUCACAGCAGAACCUUCAACAAGUUUUACAGACUCAUUGGAUGAAGAGUGCCUGAGACACUGAGGGUCAGCGCUCCAAAGAUGGAGAAGACAGAUGCCAAAGACCAGUCCUCUCAGGGGGAUGAAGAGAAAGACCCUCCGAAGAGCCACCCUUAUUCUGUGGAGACCCCAUAUGGCUUUCAUUUAGACCUGGACUUCCUCAAGUAUGUGGAUGACAUCGAGAAGGGAAACACUAUCAAAAGAAUUCCUAUCCACAGAAGGGCCAAGCAGGCCAAAUUUAGCACUCUGCCCCGAAACUUCAGCCUUCCUGACAGUGGGGCUCGCCCCCCUGCAGCCCCGCCCCUCCAAAACUGGUCUCCCGUGGUGCCAAGGGAGGCAUCACUUGGGACACAGGAGCAAAACCAGUCACCACCGCUUGGUAAUGCCCCCCAGGCCUCAACAAGCAGGAGUGAGGUGAGCUACCACAGGAAGGCUCUGUUGGCAGAGGCCACCAGACAGUUGGAAGCUGCUGAGCCAGAGGAUGCCGAGCUCACUUUUGGGAGUGGACGGCCCCAGCUCUUGAGAGCAUCCAGCAUGCCUGCCACGCUGCUGCACAGCAGGGCUUCUGAGGAGCCAGGCCUGAGCCUGGGGCCCCCUGCCCCUCCUGCCCUCCCUCCCCUUCAGGGUGAAGGCAGUGUCUGUGAUGGCACCUUUGAACCUGCAGAAGGAUUGGCAGGUUUCCACAGCUCCAGCCCACGAGCAUCAACUCGGAUUCCAGAGCUGGUCCAGGAGGGAGCUGAGCCUCCAGAGGGUGUGGUGAAGGUUCCAAAUCACCUCCCUCUCCCAGGCCCUCCUUUCUCAUUCCAGAAUGUGCUUGUAGUUCUAGAGGACAAGGAAGAUGAACACAAUGCCAGAGAAGCAGAGGUGUUGUUCACCCCUGGCUCCCCUACGCCAAGCCCGCCACCUCUGCCAUCACCCAUCCCUGAGAAUGAGCUCCUCCUGGAAGAAAUCGAGCUCAACAUCAGCGAGAUUCCACCCCCGCCACCUGUAGAGGUGGACAUGAGAAGCAUUGGCAUCAGGGUAACUGAGGAAAGCCUGGGCCUUGCCAGGGUGGAUCCAGGCAGCAUCUCCAGCCUGAAACAGCAGGUCUCGGCCCUGGAGGGAGAGUUGUCUGGAAGAACCGAGGAACUGGCACAGGUCAGAACUGCUCUCCAGCAGCAGGAAGAGGAAAUCAAAGCUAGGGAGCAAAGAAUUCGAGAGCUGGAGUUCACUGUAGCCCAACUGGAAGGACAGUUUCACCAAGAGAACGCCAAAGACACUCAGGGCCAGACGGACGUGAUGGUGAACACUGACCCUGUCCAUGGACUCUUGACCAGGGAGUCGUGUGAUAAGGGCAUUGAAGUCAACCUUCUAGGCAGCAUGGAGUCUGAAAGCUGGGGGCACCGAGGAGAGGAGAAUGGCCUCCUAUGGGGGCCAGAUGGUCAUAAACAAGGGAAUCAGAGCCCAGCAGAACGUGUGCUUCUGCCCCAGCUGUCACUGCCACAGGGACCCGAGCAGGUCCUUACCUCCUCUGUACAUAGCUUCCUCUCCACUGAACUCAGGAUUGAAGAAGCAGGCACUGAACAGGAAGGAGGCCCUCAGGGAGGAACCAGGGGAGCAGGAGGCUUUCUGUGGGGCAGCGACAGAAAGACUCCCCCAGCAGGGAGGGAGGAGACCAGUUCCAAUCUCCCAGGGAAGGAGCACCCGGGAAGGCCACCAAGCUCGCCAACGGAUGCCACUAUUGGGCAGUAUGUGAAGAAGAUCCAGGAGCUCCUGCAGGAGCAGUGGAACUGCCUGGAGCAUGGGUACCCGGAGCUGGCCAGCGCCAUCAAGCAGCCAGCCUCCAAGCUCAGCAGCAUCCAGAGCCAGCUGCUGAGCUCCCUCAACCUGCUGCUGUCGGCCUACUCGGCCCAGGCUCACCCACCCAAGGAGCCACCGGCCUCCUCCUCCUCCCCGCCAGUGGAGAUCUCCCCAUCGACCAGCCUUAAAUCCAUAAUGAAAAAGAAAGACUAUGGCUUCCGUGCAGGAGGUAAUGGGACCAAAAAGAACCUUCAGUUUGUUGGGGUUAACGGUGGGUAUGAGACCACCUCAAGUGAGGAGACCAGCGGUGAGGACAGCACCCCAGAGGACUUGUCUGACAGCGAGGCAGAGAAGAAGUGUGACGGCCCAGAUCACAAGCAUGUCAAAGAUGCCCAUCUCACCUGCGAGGCUGGGCAGGGCAUCCCUGAGGGCACCUGCCAUGCUGCCCAGGAAAGUGGGCCUGGGGAAGAAGUCCCCCACUCCAAGGCCGAGAGAUAUAAACCCUCAGAAGAAUUUCUUAAUGCAUGCCGGGCACUGAGCCAGCAUCUGCCAGAAACUGGGACCACCACAGACCAGCUCUUGAGGCAAAGCUUGAACACCAUCAGUCAAGAGUGGUUCCGCGUCUCCAGCCGGAAGUCGUCUAGCCCCGCCGUGGUGGCCUCCUACCUCCACGAGGUCCAGCCUCACUCCCCACACUUCCUGAAACUGCUUGUCAACUUGGCCGAUCACAACGGGAACACGGCCCUUCACUACAGCGUGUCCCACUCCAACUUCUCCAUCGUGAAGCUGCUGCUGGAGACAGGCGUCUGCAAUGUGGACCAUCAGAACAAAGCUGGCUACACUGCCGUAAUGAUCACUCCCUUGGCUUCCGCAGAGACCAAUGAAGACAUGGCUGUUGUCUGGAAGCUCUUAAGAGAAGGAAAUGUGAACAUUCAAGCUACUCAGGGAGGCCAGACUGCGCUGAUGCUGGGAGUCAGCCACGACAGGGAGGACAUGGUUCAAGCGCUGCUUAGCUGCCAGGCAGAUGUCAAUCUGCAGGACCACGAUGGAUCCUCGGCCCUCAUGGUGGCCUGUCACCAUGGCAACGUGGACCUGGUGCGGCUGCUCCUGGCACACCCAGCCUGCGACAGCAGCCUGACUGACAAGGCUGGCCGCACAGCUUUGUCCAUCGCUCUGAAGUCACCCACCCAUAUGGAAAUUGCUGGGCUUCUGAGAGCCCACGCGGAGCAGGGCAGGUCCCUGGGGCUGUAGGGGCUGCAGAAGAACUGGCCGUGGGGAACAAAAGCCUUCUUCUCUGGACUCCUCCCUCGCCCUUGAAGAGGGCAGAGGUCACAGGCCAGAGAGCCACCCUUCUAGAGAAGAAACUAUGUCAAAUAUGCACAUACAUUCCUGUUGUAUAAUUCUGCUCAUUAGGAUGCUUUGUAGUUUUUGCCUUAGGCCAAGCCUGAAAACUACACGGGCUUCAGAGCAGGGUUCAAGGUGCAAGGUGAGGGGUACGUCGGUGUCAUCCAAACAUCCAAAACAUCUUCAGCCUUGAAUUCCUCAUGACUCUACCCUCUGUAACAUUGUGUAGCAAGCAGGCAGGCAGGAGCACAUUAGCACAUUAGAAAAGCAAUACUUUUUACAUGGAAUUUUACAGUGCACUAUCUUUCUGUUUUUUAAGCAAGUGUAUACAAAUAUGUCCCAUUGAUAUGCAUGUCUAUAGAUGGGAGGGGAUUUAAGCCAACCCCCUGGCAAGCAUUCUGUAGGGGACCCUAGAAGAAUCACCGUGCAGACUGGUGAAACUGAACAAGCACCAUUUGGGAGCUUUGUUUCGAUGGGGUUGACAGAGAAAUCUUAAAAUCUGACAGGGUAGAAGAAGCACUUUGGCAUCAAUGCCAUAUGUACAGUCUUGACUAUUUCUGAGUCAUCUAGUGGCUCCAAUUUGCUCCAGGGAAAUUGGAAUUAAUUAAGAAAUUUAUUAUCUAGUAAGUUGCUAUGUAAUAAAGAAAAAAAAGAAAUUCAAUCCAAUGACACACACCACAUGUAUUUGGGCAGAGUCAGAUUCUCUCAGCUAUUUUGAGUCUGUGGAAGAAACAAAAAAAAGCUUCCUCCUGAGGAUGGGUUAUUGUCAUCAAGAAGCCACCUGCAUAGCCGUAUCCAUUACCUCAUGGUAAUUCCCGGUGCUUUCCCCUCAUAUCCCCUAGAAGCAAAUAUCUGUUCUGAGGUUUUUUGGGACUUCUGGCUGCAAUAGGAGCAAGGGACCCAGGCAGGGCAGAGCAAUACCUUCCGAAGCUUCCAUAUUCCCUGGGGCCAGCACAUGCAAGGUUUAUAUGGUCAGUAGCUCACGUGAAGUCAUCUGAAUCUUUCUUAAAUCUGCUCUCUUAAAAUCUCUUAUGCAAAAAAAAAAAAAAAAAGCCCCUUAUAUAAAAAGAAGUAAUGUCAAAGUUUGAUGAGCUUUACAUUGGAAACUCAAAAGCUUGCACUCUCAUUUUGGCUCAGAUGCCAAUUUGCUGGGUGCCCCUGUGGUGAGUCAUGAAACCUCCUUGGGCCGCAAUUUCAUCAUCUCUAAAAACAGAAAUUGUCAUACAACCUACCUCCUGGGAGGUGCUGCACAAGAAGCAGCUGAUGGAAGUUUCAAAAUCCAAUUUGUGGCCGAGCGCGGUGGUUCACGCCUGUAAUCCCAGCACUUUGGGAGGCCGAGGCAGGUGGAUCACCUGAGGUCGGGAGUUUGAGACCAGCCUGACAUACAUGGAGAAACCCCGUCUCUACCAAAAAUACAAAAAUUAGCUGGGGCGUGGUGGCAGGCGCCUGUAAUUCCAGCUACUUGGGAGGCUGAGGCAGGAGACUCACUUGAACCCGGGAGGCGGAGGUUUCAGUGAGCCGAGAUCGUGCCAUUGCACUCCAGCCUGGGUAACGAGCAAAACUCUGUCUCAAAAAAAAAAAAAAAAAAAAUCCAAUUUGUAACCCAUUAAGGCCAUCUACAGCAAUGGUACAGCAAACUUCUUUUGCCAUUGUGAUUCAUAAGAGAGGCUCAGAGUCCCAGAACACAAUGACAUGUGUUGAUGCAACUCAGAGGUGGAGAGAAUGGAGCAAAUAAUGAGAAAAAAAAUGCUUUAAAUGAGUUUAUUUUGACCUCAAAAUACAUUGUAAGAGCAACAUCCUACGUUAAUAAAUGUUCUAGCCCGGUGCUUCGCGAACAUUUAUGUGCAUACAAAUCACCUGGGAUCUUGUUAGAAGGCAGUAGGUCUGGGGUGGGGCCUGAGAUUCUGCAUUUCUAACCAGGUCCUGGGAGAUGCUGAUGCUAUCGAGCCACAACCACACUUUGAGUAGCAAGCCUCUGGCCUAUCCUUAUUGUUUGUUAUAUUAAAAUGCUGCCUCUCA